CCCUUCCUCGUGCUCGGCGUUGAGCUCCUGCAGCCGCCGCCGCUGCAGUGGUCGUCCCUGCCCUCCCCGGCCCCGGGGUGCACCCCGCAAGGUGAGGCCACCCCUCUGCUCCCUGCCUCCCGGUUCCUUCCCGUUCGCCGAGGUCCCCUCCCGGUCCCGGCCCUGUCCUGAGCAGUCAGUGCCUGGGACCCCAGCGGCCGUGAUGGCAGGGCUGGGGUGGGGGGCUCCGCUGUCGGGGCCGGGCCUGGAGGACUCCCCAGCACCUGAACUAGAGUGAUGUCAGGUUCCCGGGGCGCAGUGACCGUUAGCUGGUGCAGCUGGGGUGUUUUCCGCGAAGCGAUUGUCCGGGGGCAUGAGUGCGGUAGUGAGGGCGGGGGCGUAAUGGGGUCAGCGCCCCCUCCUCCCCACGACCCUGUUCAUUGCCGCUGCCUCGCUGCAUGACCUUGGACCAGUAGCAUCUCUGAGCCUCCGAGCCUCAGCACCCUCAGGAAGGAGGGCAGUGAUGUCUGGGAGUGCGGGCUCCGGAGACUCCUGCGUCAGCCGAGGCUCCCGCUGGUGUCCCUGGAGCAUGGGAGGCUGCUGAGCGUGAGUGGCGGUGUCUGGCAGGAGCUGCGUGGCAGGGAGGGCGUCCAUGGCUGCAGCCAACAAGGGCAACAAGCCCAGAGUCCGGAGUAUCCGCUUUGCGGCAGGCCACGAUGCAGAAGGAUCCCACAGCCACGUCCACUUUGAUGAGAAGCUGCAUGACUCGGUGGUCAUGGUCACCCAGGAGAGUGACAGCAGCUUUCUGGUCAAGGUUGGCUUCCUGAAGAUCCUGCACAGGUAUGAGAUUACCUUCACUCUGCCCCCAGUGCACAGGCUGAGCAAGGAUGUCCGCGAGGCACCUGUCCCCAGCCUGCACCUCAAGCUCCUCAGCGUGGUGCCCGUCCCUGAAGGUUAUAGUGUCAAGUGUGAGUACUCGGCGCACAAAGAGGGCGUCCUCAAAGAGGAGAUACUGCUAGCCUGCGAAGGUGGCACUGGCACCUGUGUGCGCGUGACGGUGCAGGCCCGCGUCAUGGACCGGCACCACGGCACGCCCAUGCUGCUGGAUGGUGUCAAGUGUGUGGGCGCCGAGCUGGAAUACGACUCAGAGCACAGCGACUGGCACGGCUUUGACUGAGGCCCGAGGCCCCGCCUGCCCCGGGCCCCUCAGCCUUAAACCCCGCCUUGUCCCCCCGACAUGCUGCGUGAUGGUGUGGCUUCCUCGCCCCUCUCUGGGGUGGGUGUGGGGGUGGAGUGGCCUUGCCCACGCCUCUCACCUCUGCCUUCAUUUGUGCUGCCACCCUGCCCCUCCCUCGUCCUCCUCUCCCACUUCCUCCUCUCUGUGUGCCUCAGUCUCCUGCCGGAAGAAAUGGGUUGAGCCCGAAAGGAGGCUGUCUGAGGAAGGGAGAGGGAGGGCCUGGGGUGGGUCCCCCACUCCCCACCCCAAGCCACAGGGACUCCCACCAGGGUCUGGGAGAGGACGGAGCUGGCUCUGUGGCGUCGUGGCCCCAUUACUGCUGCCUUGCUUCAGCCACCUCUCCUGCCCCUCCCUAGUCCCCACUGCUGUCCACCAUGAGUAGGAGGGAGGUGCAGUCCCCAGCCCCCACCCCUCAGGUCUGUGUUACUUGGUUUUUAAGCGACUGGUUGGGAUAGAACCCUAAAGAAAUAAACUUCCAGUGGAUACCGGA